AUGGUAACCGGUCACCGCUUCUAUGGAGUGGCGUUUACUACCAAUUGCAAAUAAGAAAAUUCCAGAUUCCAUUCCAAGAUGGCCAAAUAGGAACAGCUCCAGCCUGCAGCUCCCAGCGUGAUUAAUGUAGAAGAUGGGUGAUUUCUGCAUUUCCAACUAAGCUGAAAAUGGCAAAAACAGGAGCAGAAGAUCACAGAGAAGCACUAUCUCAGUCUUCCUUAUCCCUCUUGACUGAAGCAAUGGAAGUAUUACAGCAAAGUAGCCCUGAAGGCACUUUGGAUGGGAAUACUGUAAACCCAAUUUACAAAUAUAUUUUGAAUGAUUUACCAAGAGAGUUUAUGUCAUCCCAGGCAAAAGCAGUUAUUAAAACUACUGAUGAUUAUUUGCAGUCUCAGUUUGGCCCCAACAGACUCGUGCAUUCAGCAGCAGUAUCAGAAGGGUCAGGACUUCAAGAUUGCUCCACACAUCAAACAGCAUCAGAUCACAGCCAUGAUGAAAUAUCAGACCUAGAUAGCUACAAAUCAAACAGUAAAAACAAUUCUUGUUCUAUAUCAGCAUCCAAGAGAAACAGACCUGUCAGUGCUCCAGUGGGUCAACUGAGGGUUGCAGAGUUCUCUUCUUUAAAAUUUCAGUCAGCCCGGAAUUGGCAGAAAUUGUCUCAAAGACACAAACUUCAACCAAGAGUGAUUAAAGUAACAGCUUACAAAAAUGGAUCUAGAACAGUCUUUGCCAGAGUUACUGUACCAACCAUCACCUUGCUGCUGGAGGAGUGCACAGAAAAGCUGAAUCUGAACAUGGCCGCAAGACGAGUGUUCUUGGCAGACGGCAAGGAAGCCCUCGAACCUGAAGAUAUACCCCAUGAAGCCGAUGUUUAUGUUUCAACGGGAGAGCCCUUUUUAAAUCCAUUCAAAAAAAUUAAAGACCAUCUGUUGUUAAUUAAGAAAGUAACUUGGACAAUGAAUGGGUUGAUGCUUCCUACUGAUAUCAAAAGACGGAAAACCAAGCCUGUUCUUUCUAUUAGAAUGAAGAAACUUACUGAGAGGACCUCAGUCCGAAUUCUGUUCUUUAAGAAUGGCAUGGGGCAGGAUGGGCAUGAGAUUACAGUGGGAAAAGAAACAAUGAAAAAGGUUUUAGAUACUUGUACAAUAAGAAUGAAUCUAAAUUUACCAGCCAGAUAUUUUUAUGAUUUGUAUGGCAGAAAAAUUGAAGAUAUUUCAAAAGUUCCUCUGCUUGAAAAAUGCCUGCAAAAUUCCAUCACACCUUUGCGAGGACUACUUUGGGUCUCUAAGGGAGAAGGUUUCAGCCCCUCAGGAGCUAAGAUGUACAUCCAAGGAGUUCUUUUGGCCCUGUACCAACGAUUAAAGUCUGCAAAAAAAUAUUAUAAACAGUUGAACCUGGUCAUGAAUGAACAGAAGGAGAAAAUUACAGAAAAAGUCAUUCUUUCAAUGACGGCAAAGGAACACCAUAAGGAACAGGAAGAAGUGAGCAGGCUGAUUGAUGAAUUGCAGACAGCUAUCAAAAGUAACAUAGGUCAUCUCUGUAAACUUGGCCCCCAAUUACAGGCUGAGCAGGAGCAAUUCUCCUCUUAUGUCUACCAACACAUUAAAAGCCUUCCAGCAAACACGCUUGUCCCAGGAGGCCUGCAGCUUAAGGUAUUUGAAAAUGGUAAAAACACUGGAGAGAUCUCUGUUGGUAUCAGUAAAAAAGAUUUGGGAUCGGAUAGCCCAAUUCAAACUGACCAUAUGAUGGAAAGAUUACUUCUCAAGAUUCAUCAAAGGCUUCAAGGUUCUUCCAUCAACCCACCAGGCCUCAAUUAUUCUUCAAUGCGGCUUUUUGAUGAGAAUGGCCAAGAAAUUAAGAAUCCACUUUCGCUGAAGAAUGAGCAAAAAAUUUGGGUCUCUUAUGGUAGAGCAUACAGAUCUCCACUAAAUCUUGCUUUGGGUUUGACCUUUGACCGAGUGAGUGCAUUUGCCAGAGGUGAUAUCAUGGUUGCAUAUAAGACCUUUUUGGAUCCUAAUGCUGUUCUGCUACCUGGAUGUGGCAAUUGGGAAGUUUGUGAGGGAUUUCCAAUUAAUUUCAACUGUACCAGUCAACAGAUACCUGACCAGUUUGAAAAGGUGGACUUGGAGAACCAUUUUCUACAGAACAAGGUAGAUCCCAAUAUUGUCCUUCAUGCCUCUGUUUCCAUUGGAAAGUGGAGUUUCUCAGGCAGUGAAGCAAGCAGCAGGAGUCAAAUAGCGCCAUCGAUCCUGUGGCCUGUAGCCAGUGUGUGGCUGAUCACCAAGACUGGAAUGAUCCUGAGCCGAGCGAUAACUCAGGGCUGCCUGGCUAUUGGUCAUCCUAUCAGAGUCAAGGCUGCUGAGGGAACAUCACUAGAAGGAUAUAAAUUAAUCUUACAGAAAAGACAUAGUGGAGAUGACUCUCAGAAGUGGGUGUUUGGAACUGAUGGUUGCAUUUAUUCAAAGGCUUAUCCUCAGUUUGUUCUGACCUACCUAGAGGAGCUAAAUGCACAAGUAGAUGUGACCCAGACAGAGUAUCACAUUCACCAUGGUGCCUGGACCACAGCUCAUCAGGAACAUGGCAGAAACUUAGCAGAAGAGGUUCUGCAAGAAAGUGCCAGCAACCUUGGUCUGAAGCAACUGCCAGAACCCUCAGACACCCAUUUAAUGCCAGAAGGUUCUCUUGAGGAGACGGGGGAGCUGACAGUAGCACUGGUGAGGAAACUGGAAGAGAAACAUCCUAAGGCUUCUGCUCAGAGGUGGGCCAUAAAACAUGAAGGAACCAGUAAGCCAGGCCAGUGGAAACAUUCUAGAGUUGAAAAUCCUCUAUGGAACAAGCUUACCUACAUGUGGCCUGUCCUUCCCAGUGGCCAACUUAAUGAGGAGUUUGAUUGGCCAAUACAAGGACUGCUUGUUCCGAGCAGUCCUCCCAUGAAGAAACCCAUCUGUAAGACAACAGAGCCAUAUGCCCCUGUGCGACUCAGAGUUUUGCAGAAUGGAGAGAAGAAUAAAAACAGAUCCGUUACUAUCCUUGGUCCAGAUAUCUCACCUGGACGGAAAACGCAGUGCACUGAGAUUUUAAAUUUACCUUCUGCAGCUCGGAGAUUGUACAAUGAAAAGGGGAAGGAAAUAUUUGCCUUAAAAGACCUGCAAAGAGAUGAACUGGUGUAUGUUUCAUGUGGAGAACUCUGGAUCAAUCCUGACCUGUCCAUUGCUCAGCAAAAGAAACAAAUAUUCCUGAGGAACCUAGAAUCAGACAUUGCCAAAAUUCAAAUCUUCUGCAGCACACAUAAAAUAGAAGCUCUUGUUUUAGAAGUCCAAAGUGACAUUGUAUCUGGAAGCAAGCUUGCUGUGCAUAAACCUGUAGCAAUUUUUGGAGAAGAGAAGCAAGUUACAGAACCGGAAGAAAAGCAAAUGCAAGAAGAUCCUCUAACAACGGAAAAUGCUUCCAGUGAAAUUCUAGAUUCACACGUAAGAGCUCAUCUUCGAAUGAAGGCUUGUCACACACUUCCCAGGUAUGCCUGGCAGGAAACUUCACAUGACUUUGAUGAGGAUGACAGUCUUCCAAAGAAAACGGAAAAAGGGCUCUUUGAAAAUGUGGAACCACAGAAGAAACACAGCUGUUCACCAAAGCAUAGUAAAUUGCACAAGCAUUGUCAUCAGCAGUUCGAAUACAGAGAUGGGCAGAUUAUAAGCCAUGCUGCUCCUCAGCUAGUCUUGGGGGUUCAAGGUCCCAAUCUCCGAUCAGGCAUGGAGGUGGUUUUGGUGGAGAAGAAAUCUGAUGGUAGUCAUCAGCGCUGGAUACACCAGGAAGACAGCAGGACCUUUCACCUUGUGAGUAACCCUGACCUUGUGCUGGCAGUGUCUAUGACCAAGACUAGAAAUGAAGUUUGUGGCUAUCCAGUUAUUGUUCAGAAAUAUAAGCCGUACAACAAUGGAGCUGCCAAUCAAAAGUGGCAUUACAUGAAAAAUAUAAAAGCACUUGUGGCCUUUCAUAGCACUGCCUUGGAUAAGGAAAUUACAUCAGCAAAUUAUGCUGGUGUCUGUACAUCAUCUGUGAUUAAAGAAGAAAACAUUGAUCAACCAGGAUACUGUUAUCUCUCACCUGAUGGAAAGAGAAAAACUAUGCUCUGCUUGGCUUGUGGACAAUCCAUGAGAACAGAGAAAGGACUGAAACAAUUGCUUCCAGGGGUUCCAUUCCUCUGUAUUUCAGGCACCAAGACUCAGAAGCCCUUCUUACAAGGGCCCUUCAAGGUCAUCAGUGUGGCUGAGGUUGAUUUGUCGUGUGACAAGGCUGAAAAAACUCUAAGUUACUACCAAGCACGUCUAUUGUCUUUACGGAUGAAGACCUGCACGCAAGCUGCAUCUCACAGUGGCAUGGCAGCCACACACCAGAAGGCAGUGAAAAUAAUUGCAUACAAAAAUGGGGAUGGGUAUCGUAAUGGGAAGUUAAUUGUGGCUGGAACAUUCCCCAUGCUUCUUACAGAAUGCACGGAACAACUUGGGCUUGCCAGAGCAGCCUCCAAAGUAUAUACCAAAGAUGGAACCCCAAUCUUUACCUUGCGUGAUUUGGUUUUAUGGGCUCUAGAUGAAUCCUUUCUCCAGAGAGACUCUGAGAAACAAAAGCAAGAUGCAGCUCCUGUUGGAAAAGAACAGAUAAUUGUUGAAAGUAUGGAAGAAAAUCCAAGAAUGAAAGUGAAAAACAGAUUAUUUGCAAAAUCUGUGACAUCCGAUAGUUUGGAUGGUAUAGACAAGUCUUUGCUUACCCUCAUCCUCAGAAAUCCUAUUGCCAUCUGGGUGUCUUGUGGUGAACCAUUUCUACCUCCAAAUGCUUUGCAGAAAGCAGAAAAAUUAGAGAAACAGAACUGGCUAAAAAAGGACAGAAUUUUGGCUGAUCUAGAUACCAUGAGACACAAAAUGAGACAGUUAAAAGGGCGGCGAGUAGCGGCAUGUCAGCCAGCCACCAUGGUUCCUACCAAGAGCCCUGUGCAGCCCGUGGUGGUUGAAGGAGGCUGGACCGAACAGACUCAACAGGAAAUUAAACUCAUGGAACUUAUAAGACAUACAGAGGCACACCUUUCUGAAAUCCAAGAAAUGGAAUCCAAAAUAAAUUUUCCAAUUGCAACCAAACGUAUAGCAGUCAAGCCGAGCAACCUGUAUAAGCAGCCCAACACAAAACGAGUGUGGAUUUAUCUAAAUGGAGGCAGACCUGAAGAUGGCACUUAUGCCUGGGGCAAAACUAUUUCAGAGCUGCUGCAAGACUGCUCCUCUCGUCUCAAAAUGACCCACCCAGCUAGAGCACUGUACACCCCCAGUGGAGAGCCAAUUCAGUCCUGGGACGACAUAGAGCGAGAUAUGGUCAUCUGUGUGUCUAUGGGACAUGGUUUCAAAACCCCAAAAGAGUUAAAACAACUGAUGGAGAUCAGAGCAAAUUAUGCCAGAAUCCGAAGGCAGCAGGGCCCUCAAGCCACAGACAUUGUGGUGUCACCAUCCACGAAGCUGCUGUCUCUGGCACAUCUCCACAAUUAACUCCUAUCAGAACCAUCGGAUUUUCUGCUGUAUUUUUCUGCUGAUUCCUGGAAGUUCAUCUGCUUAGUAGGUCCUUUCUACAGGUGCUCACCAGGAUCUGCAUAUGGGGUCACCUUCACCUUCAGAAGCCCAAUUUAAAUCUCACCAGAGCAACAGAGGGAGGUCAUAGCAUGACUUUGUGGUAGCCAAGGUCUGGAGGUCACUCCUUCCAGGGAAAGAUUCCUGGACUUGGAGACAAAGGCCUGACUUGAGUCUUACCUUCCUGCAGUCUUGGGAAAGUUUCUUGGCAUAAGACUCAAAUGAGAUCAUCAACACAGGAAGAGAAGGGCACUAACAUUUUUAGAGUGUCUACCUGUACCGGGCACCAUAAUGGACUUUUACAUAAAUGUUGUCUGUCUCAUUCAGUAUUCACAACCACCCUACGAAGUAGAUAUUUCUUCUACUACUUUUACAUUUUACAGACGGGAAAGCUGGGCUUUCAAGAAGUGAAAUAUCUUUGCUAAAGGCACCAGCCAAUAAGUGGCAGAACUGGGAUUUAUACCCAAAUCUGCCUAACCUCAAAGCCUGCUUUUUCCAUUUAGGUUCCCUAGAAACCCCUUGUAAGUUUUCAGUGCAAUAGAAAUGUUAGAUGUGGUCUUGGUAAUUCUGAAAAUGAGUUCACUAGAUGCCUUGAAGUGAUCAUUUUUAUGGUUUAGUUGCCGCUUAUUUGGAUGACUUUCCUGAUGACAACUGAGUUAGGCAAGGUAAGCUACAUUUGGAUGCCCAACCCAAGGUGUGAGAACAGAAAUCUAUUUCUCACAUUUCUGGAGGCUGGGAAGUCCAAGAUCACAAUCAAGGCACUGGUGUAUGGUGAGGGUCUUCUUACUGCUUCCCCACAGGGCAGAAAGUGGAAGGGCAAGAGAAAGCAAACCCACUCCCACAUGCCCUUUUUAUAGCAGCAUUAAUCCAUUUAUGAGGGUAAAUCCCUCAUGACCCAAAUACCUCUCAAAAUGCCCCACUUCCCAACGUUGUUGCAUUGGGGAGUCAGUUUACAGAACAUGACUUUUGGAAGUCAUAUUCAGACCACAGUAGGUGCCAUAAUUAAGUACCACAAGAGGGGUAGCUUAAACAACAAAAGUGUGUUGUCUCACAGUUCUGAAGGCUGGAAGUCCAAGAUCAAGGUGUUGGCAGCACUGAUUCCUUCUGAGGGCUAUGAGGAAGAAUCUGUGCCAUUCCUCUCCUUAGUUUCUGAUGAUUUGCUGGUGCUGUGGACUGAAAAUUUGUGUCCCUCCAAAAUUCAUAUGUUGAAACCCAAUCCUCAAUGUAAUAGUAGUAAGAGCUGGGACCCUUAGGGGCUAAUUAAGUCAUGAGGGCAGUAGCCUCAUGAAUGGAAUUAGUGCCCUUAUAAAAUAAGCCCAAGAGAGCUGCCAUGCCUCUUCCACUAUGUGGGGACACAGCAAGAAGGCACCAUUGGAACCAGGCACCAUAUGAAACAGGAAGCAAGCCCUCACUAGACACCAAAUCUGCCGACACCUUGAUCAUAGACUUCCCAGCCUCCAGAACAGUGAGAAAUAAAUUUGUAUUUUUUCUAAGCUACCCAGUCUAUGUUAUUUCAUGAUAGAAACCUGAAUAGACUAAGAAAAGCUGGCAAUCUUUUGACAUUUCUUGGGUUGUAGAAGCAUCACCUCAAUCCCUGCCUUCAUAUUUAUGUGACAUUCUUCCUGUGUCCUUGGGUCCAAAUUUUCCCAUUGUUGUAAGGACAUCAGUGAUACUGGAUUAGGGGCCCACCCUAGUCUAGUGUGACUUCAUCUUACCUAAUUACAUCUGCAAUGAUCUUAUUUCCAAAUAAGAUCACAUCCUGAGGUGCUGGGGGUUAGGAUUUUGACAUGUGAAUUUUGGGGGAAUGCAAUUCAACCCAUAAUAAUCAGUAACAAAAAUCCCCAAACCUCACCCACACAAGCCUUCUUCAUAGCACAAGUGCCCUACCAUUAAAGAUUGCAACAUUCUUUCUUGAUGACAUGCCUCUCUCUUUUAUGUCUUUCUUGUUCCUUACUAACACUGAUGUCUGAUAUUAAUGGAAAAACCAUUAAAAAAAAAACUAUUAUCCUAUGAGGUAAAUUGAAUGCACUCAACUGUAAAAGGAAGACUUAUCGAUCAAUUUUAGUUAAACCUUGCUUGUCUGACACUUUGCUGCUAAGGAAUGUGUUUUUAUUGCCUGGCCAGAUAGUUCAGAUUUCCGGUCAGUCUUAGUAAAGACCCCUUUUAUAACAUUGAUAAAAUUUUAUCACAGAGCUAUGAAAACAAAAUUAGAUUUCAUAACUCACAUCAGGCCUUGAAGGGGAUGCCUCUAUAAAUUUUACAAACCCUAUCAAGUUUAAUGCACCUAUUCUGAUAAUUUUUUCAAUAGCAAAUUCUACUGAACUUCAUAUAUACUAUGUGUGUAUAUAAAUGUGUGUAUGUGUGUGCGUGUGUUCAUGUAUAUACAUAUAUAUAGAUUUGUUUCU